GGGGAGUCUGAGGAACCUGCAGCCCCGGCCUCGCCCCUGAGGUGUGGGAAGCCGAAGGUCCCGUUGAGUGUGGUUGGCCUUGACUCGGGCGUUGCACCGGCAUGAUCGCAUUAGCCUCACUGGUUAUGGGUAGCUGCUGCUGGGAGCGUGGUUACGGGUGAGGAAACUGAGGCCCAGAGAUGGGGAGUCACCUGCCCGAGGUUACGCAGCUCAUAACGGGGACAGCAGGUUCCUGCAUCCCCAGAUUAGCAGGCCCCAGAGACCCUGUGUCCAACCUGGAGCUGCCCAUUUCCACGCUUGAUGCCCCUGAGUCCUUCAGGCUAAAACCAGUAUUUAUUGAGAAUGGAAGAUGUGCCGGGCCCAGCAGCCGGCCGUUUAUCUGUUAUCCUCCCCGCAACUCAGCAAGUGCAAUGGGUUCCUCUCCACUUUGCAGGUAGAGAAACUUAGACACAGAGCAGUUAGAGGCCCUAAAGUGACUCAGCUAGUAAGAAGCAGAGCUGGAGUUCAAACUCAGGCUGCAGAAGAUGUCAAUGUUACUUUCGAAGAUCAACAAAAGAUAAACAAAUUUGCACGGAAUACAAGUAGAAUCACAGAGCUGAAGGAAGAAAUAGAAGUAAAAAAGAAACAACUCCAAAACCUAGAAGAUGCUUGUGAUGACAUCAUGCUUGCAGAUGAUGAUUGCUUAAUGAUACCUUAUCAAAUUGGUGAUGUCUUCAUUAGCCAUUCUCAAGAAGAAACGCAAGAAAUGUUAGAAGAAGCAAAGAAAAAUUUGCAAGAAGAAAUUGACGCCUUAGAAUCCAGAGUGGAAUCAAUUCAGCGAGUGUUAGCAGAUUUGAAAGUUCAGUUGUAUGCAAAAUUCGGGAGCAACAUAAACCUUGAAGCUGAUGAAAGUUAAACAUUUUAUAAUACUUUUUUUAUUUGUUUAAUAAACUUGAAUAUUGUUUAAAAUGAUAAUUUUCCUUCUUCAAAUGACAUGGAAAGCAAAACUUUCUUUUUUAAAAAUUUUCAUUUAUUUAAUGGAAACUUGCCCAUUUUCACAUGUCUGCUUAUUUAUUUUAUAUUUUUAAAAGAAGACAGUAUUCACCUAUGUAUUUUGCAUAACGAUUAUAUCAAGUCUAGGGGCUUCAUGUCAUGUUAUUAAAAUCAGUUAAGCAAUCUUUUAUGUUUCUAUAUUAUUUAGAAUAUUUGUUGUUGCAAUUUUCACAUAAGAAAAUUUAACAGUUGUGUCAUGUUGUUUCUGUCUGAUUUUAAUUGCUGUCUAAUGACGGGGAAAGCACGAUGAAAAGAUGUACAAUCCUGCAUCCUUGCUUAUUUCACAACUAAAGCUUUGUCAUAGACUUCAAAAUAUAUAUGUAUAUAUUUUAUUUAAAUAUAUGUUACAUAUUAUAUUUAAACAUACAUAUUUAACAUUUUUUACAUAUCUAUCAAUAUCAGAGAUUUGGGUAAAAGAAUGGGUAAUGUUUAAACAUGUGGAGGCAUGUGGAGCUUUAUACAAACAGGGCAGAACCACAGAAGAACGUUUUAGAAACCAAGAGAUGUGCAGAAAGAAAUGUUUAGUGUUUUUUCGUUUUAAAUUUUAGAUUUUAUUUUAGUGCUUUGUAAUUAAUUGGGGUUUAUAUUGAUAAAGAUGUGGAAGUUAAACAGCUAUGUAUGUAAAAGUAAGGCUUAUUUCUUAAAUAAAGGAUGCAUUUCUUCCCACUCCCCCA